CUUCCCGCCGCCGCUCUCGCCCGGGCCGGCCAUGGCGCUCAACAAUUUCCUUUUCGCUCAGUGCGCCUGCUACUUCUUGGCCUUCCUGUUCAGCUUCGUGGUGGUGGUCCCGCUGUCCGAGAACGGCCACGACUUCCGCGGCCGCUGCCUGCUCUUCACCGAGGGCAUGUGGCUGAGCGCCAACCUCACGGUGCAGGAGCGCGAGCGCUUCACGGUGCAGGAGUGGGGCCCGCCGGCCGCCUGCCGCUUCAGCCUGCUCGCCAGCCUCCUGUCUCUGCUGCUGGCCGCCGCGCACGCCUGGCGCACGCUCUUCUUCCUCUGCAAGGGACACGAGGGGUAAGUGGGGGCCGCUCCCGGCGCGGCGCCCCUUCCAUGCCCCCAGCGCCCCCAGACCCACCUCCCCGGGGAGGCGCGCGAGUCCCUCCGUCUCUCAGGCAGCUCCGAGGCCCGCAAAUGUCAACAAUCCGCCCUCACCCCCUCCACUCAGACCGCCCUUUGUCUACACACACAUCCAGGGACCAUGACGACCACCGGUCCUGCGUACAAGGCCAGUGCCUCCCCUCCCCAGCUGCGCAUCACCUCCCGCUUCCGGGCAUCUGCUCCCUUGGGUUGCAGAUGUUGCACUGUCAUCACCCAGCAGGCCUGGACCUUCCUGGGCGGGCUCAGCCGGGCCACACUCGCCAGGACCGGCGACAACUCCCAGCCCGGUCUAGGGCUUGCACUGAGCUCUCCAGGUCCCAGUGACAAGGCGAACUGGGGAGCCCCACCCGGCACCAUCGCCCCGGGAAAGGGACGGCAGAUGGCUGUCUGGAGGGGAGCCACCCAGGCCCACCUCGAGCUCAGGCCUUGGAUGGGGAGCUGGAGAGAGACUGCAGGGCGAGGGCUGUGCCUUGUGGGCUCAGCGCCUUCCUCCUCCUGGCCUGCAUUUUCCUCUUUCUCUUUCCUGCUCCGGCUAGAUACUGGAGCCCAUACAACCUGGUUCACCUGGGGUGCGGUGACACCCUUAGCCAGUGGCACCCUGGGGGCCCUCUGGGGGCCCACCCACUCCCUCUGCAGGUGCUCUCUGUGAACCCUCCCACUCCCUCUGUGAGCCCACCCACUCCCUCUGUGAACCCACCCUCUCCCUCUGUGGGUGCCCUCUGUGAGCCCAUCUACCACCUCUGUGAAUCCACCCACCCCCUCUGUGAACCCACCCACCCCCUCUGUGAGCCCACCCACCCCCUCUGUGAGCCCACCCACUCCCUCUGUGAACCCACCCACUCCCUCUGUGGGUGCCCUCUGUGGGCCCUCCCACUCCCCUGGCUGAGGCCUGCUGUGCCCAGGAGCAGCCCGAGAUCCUGUAGAGGUUCCGGGAGAGCACUCAUGAAACCCAGGCUCCUCCCAAACUCUGCCCUCACCCCCAUCCUUUGUUGUAGGUUUUCACUUCCUGCACGCAGGUGGGAGAUGAGAAGGGCUCAGAGGGGUGUGGGCGGCAGGAGUGGGGAAGCCCUCCUGUUGCCCCCGCUGUGAGCCCACCGCUUGGUUUUGGCUGAGAGAGGGGCCAGAGAGGGGAAGAAGAGGGGCUUCAGGGAGAAGGGAGGGAGCCAGGGCUAUGCUGAGUGGGGCUGCAAACUCUGGAGGAGGAAUGAGAAUCCCAGCGCCUGUGGGUAGGAGCGCCCUGGGGCUGCUGCAGCACAGUUGCACCAACUGGACUGAAACCCACUUGUCCCACCACCCUCUGCCGCUGUCCUCACAGGGCGCCUUUGCUCUGCUCUGUCCUCCCUCUUUUUACAGGGACACCAGUCACUGGAUUCAGGGCCCACUCUAAACUCAGGGAGAUAUCCUGAGAUCCAGAGCUUAAUUACACCUGCAAAGAUGCUAUUUCCAAACAAAGUCACAGUCACGGGUACCAGGGGUGGGACUUGGGCAUAUCUUUCGGGGGACACCAUUCAACCCACGACACUAAGGUUCUGGAUGGGGGUCAGUAGAAAGCUGGCUGUCAGCCUGGGAGGACCCAGGUACUGUGGGGCCAUGGGCCCAAAUUGUGUGGCUGGAGCCCUGCUCAAGGUGGGGUCAGGCCGGGCGCAGGGUGGUGUCCUGCCCAUUUGCAGCCGUCCUCCUUCCCUCAGCCCACUCCAGGGCUGGUGUCCCAAGAAGAGGCUUGAGACGUCAUCUGCACCCAUGUUGCCAAACCCAAGAGUUGCCCAGUCCAUGCUGUGCAUGCAGGGCAGGCAGGUGGAAGCCUCCCUGAAUGAGACAGGUGUGAAGAGGGAGUGGGACAGCCAGCGAGUAGGGUCAGCCUCCCAACGCUUGAGGUCCCUUUAGUCUGGGAAGCUGAGGGUGGAGGGUGCAGGCCAGGUGGGGCCACAGUUGGUUCAUCGCUCACGCACUUCUUCACCUCCUGGGUGUCCCUCAGGGUGCCUGUGGUCCAGCUGGGGCUGACAGAGGGUGGCUCUCUAGAUAGGACCCAGCUAUGUGGUCAGAGUGAUGGGAGAUUUUAUAGGGGGUUCCACCAGAAGCUGGGGGACAGGGAGAGGGGAGAAAAGAGCCCCAGAGCUUGCAAGACAGGAGUCCAGGUCGCACAGGGUAUGGUCUAUUUCGCACACACUGGGCGGCAGGCCCAGGGAUGCCGUAACAGCAGCUCUGCCUCUUGCCAUCUCACGGAAGGUGACUGUCUGUCAGCCGUGGCAAACUGCCAGCACCAUCUCCUUCCAAAGGCAGAAAACAGAUUCCUGGGGAGUCUGCAGGCCUUCCCAGCACUCUUUGUGGUGUUCCAUCCUCCCAAGGGGUGGAGCCGGCUGGGAUGCAGGCCAGCUGUGUGGCCUCUGCUGCAGCCCUGCUGACCGGCCCAUAUGGGAUUUAGGAAGCCUUAGACGGCCUGGUAUGCUCAGGCCUGUGGGGGUUAGGGUGAGGGUUAGGGUUGUCGAGGGGGGCUACAUUGUGGAGGCUCACCAUGGCCUUGACCCCACUGGAGGUCAGGUCCGGGCAGCUCCUGCUGUCAGGAAGGGGCCUGUGGCGGAGCAUUUCAGGUUCAGCUCCUUUGCUUCAGUUCAGGGGUUCACCAAUCCUCCCACCACUGACCUCCGCCCAGCCUGCUCUUUUCCAGGGACAUCUGGUGCCUGUGUCCUUCUUGACCAUCAGGAAUUAGUGGCUCAGUUCACGUGGUCAUGUGGCCACCUGUCCCCCACCUCAUGCACUGCACAGUCCAUUGGCAGACGGCUUGUGGGGUGACAUCUGUCAAACGUGUCAGCACUCCAUUGAGUUCUGGUUGUAGGCGAAGGUUAACGCUCUCAAGAGCCAUCUCAGGCCAUGGGUCCCCCCCCAGGGGACCCCACCCUAGGGGACCCACAGCUGGGUGAAGCCAAGGCAGACAUGCACCUUAUUCAUCUCUGUGUCCUUAGGGCUGAGCACAGGGGAUGGUGCGUAGGAGUCCCCAGAUAAUGUUUGUUGAAUGACUGACAGAAAGAUGCCUGGGUCCUGAGGCCUGCUGCCUUGUGGUCACUCACCUGGCCCCGAUACCUGUGCAGACUCAGUUAUCUGGCCAACAGGUCCACCCUUCAGACUUGCCAUGUCAGGAAGUUCUGGACCCCUGGGAAGAUGGGGUCUGCAGGGUCCAGCGACAGAGCAGCCAAUUCCAACUCAAUUGUUGGUCCAGCUGCAUAGACUAGGUGAGCAAGUGCCAGGUAGGUAAAGGGGACUCAGGACCAGCCACGGAGCUGAGACGGGCCUUUACAGGGAGCUCAUGUGGUGGACAAGGGCUCUCAGGGCCAUCGACGGCCACUGGACGUCCAGCCCAGGGAGGAGCCCACUGACCCCAUCAGACUCUGGCUGCUAGAGGUCUGGGCCUGUUUAGGACAGCACAUGCUCUAACCCUCUAAAGGGGACUCCACCUCCAGGGGCCACCCGGCUGCCCUCCUGCCAGUGUGAGGGCAAGGCCUGUGUGAGGUCUGUUUGAGGGGCACAUGGCACGUCCAGAGCUUGUGGAGCAGAGGCCAUGUCUCAGGUGCCAGCUUCCUCUUCCUAUGGGGGUGUCUUUCAUGCAGAGUCUGGGCCCUGAGAGCUCGUGCCCAGAAGUGUGAAAAUUAGUCUGGGGGUAGCUUUUUGCAGAGGAGUGUCAUCUUGAUGCUCCAUUAUUGGCUGCUGAGUGAAUGAGUGAAUGAAUGAAUGAAUGAAUGAAUGAGUAAAUGAAUGAAUGAAUGAAUGAAUGAAUGGAUGAAUGAAUGGAAUGGCACCUGUGCUUCAGAGAGGCUUGCCAUUUCGGGGCAGAAGGGUUUGCUGAGGCAGCCGUGGGCCUGGGGCAGCUGUGCUGAGGGAGGAUUGAGCACGUGGGCUGGCAGCAGUUUGUGGUUGGCGGGCCGGAGGGAUGCUGCGUUAAACUCAUCUGCCUGCCCGUGCCGGCGCUGAGCCUUCACAUUGCUGGGCUUUCCAGGACAGCGGUCACCAUGGAGAUGGCACAUCCUGGCAGGGCACCCUGAGCGGCAGUGAAGAGAGACAGGGUUAACCCUGCAUGUGCCGGGCUCCUGUUCCUGACCACUGUCCUGGCCUGGCCUUGGUGAGGGAGGGGCUGGGUGGCCCUGUGACCUCUGGGGAGCUGGAUCCGGGGAUGCUCUGGACACAUCCAAUUCUUCAACGACCUGGACAGCCUGGGCAGGAUCCCUGGAAACCGACCAGAAAGGAAUGAGAGGAACAGACCGAGGCUGUCAGCUGGCAGCGGCCCCAGCCUGGGGUCCCUUCCCUAUCUCAUGGGGAACUCCUCGAUCUGGUCAUGGGAGAAGACUCCAAAAUCGGGCCAUUUCAUAGGGAGAGCUUUGGAUGUGGCGCUGUGAUGGGGGUUGUGGCUUGUCUACUGGCACACGGUACCCACUCUCCAGCCAUCUUCAGCCAUGAGGCCUGGGCAGAGGCUCGGUCACCCCCCACGCGUACGUGUGUGAGUCCUGCUGGUCCUGCCCUCGUUGGUGUGGUUGUUGGAUCACAGCCCAUGGCUUUAAGAGUGUCCCUGUGUCCUCUCCCCUUGUCUGGGACUCCCUGGGGUGGCUCAAACCCUCCCGUUCCUGGGGGGUGGUUCUGCUGUCAGCCCAGCAGUCACCAAAACAGUGUGUCCGGGACUGGGGCCAGUGGACGGGCUCCUUGGAGGCACCAGAUGUUACAAAGCAGCCUGGUGUCGCCUGCUCUGAGUUGGGCGCUGUGGCCUGGGUUUAUCCUCAGCACGUUGGCUGGGGCACCUCCCGGGGCCAGGACUUCGUCUUUUGUAUCACUCUGCCCUCUGUGUCCAGCACAGGGCGAGCAGGUGCUCAGAAAGUGCCUGCUGAAUGAAUGAACAGACAAUGCGCUGGCCUCCACUUUGCCUCAUCAGCAGCUGCCGAGUUCGGAUGACGGUAGCGUUGAUGUUUUCUUGGCUGAGAUUCCAGGGAGACCUUGUUUAUUAAAUGAUCGCUGUGAAGCUGUUUCUGUGGGUCACCUCCCUUAGAUCCAGUGUGCUGACAGCAUGCAGGCUAACAUCGAGCCUGCUGGCAGGCUGGGGUCUUGUAAACAACAGGCAUUUACUGCUCACACUUCCGGAGGCUAGAGGUCUGCGAUCCAGGCUGGGAUCCAGCUCCUUCUUCUCCGCCUUCCUGAACCUCCUGGUCAGCGCCUUCGUGGUCUUCCUGGUCUUCAUUGCCAGCACCAUCGUGAGCGUGGGCUUCACCAUGUGGUGCGACACCAUCACCGAGAAGGGCACCGUACCCCACAGCUGUGAAGAGCUCCAGGACAUCGACUUGGAGCUGGGCGUGGACAACUCCGCCUUCUACGAUCAGUUUGCAAUUGCCCAGUUUGGCCUCUGGGCCUCAUGGCUGGCCUGGCUGGCCAUCACCACGCUGGCCUUCCUGAAGGUCUACCACAACUACCGUCAGGAGGACCUGCUGGACAGCCUGAUCCACGAGAAGGAGCUGCUGCUGGCCCGGCCGUCCCCACGCACCUCCUUCCAAGAGGAGAAGAGCGCUGUCAUUUAGGCACAGUGCAGGCAGGGGGAGCUGGCCCCGACCUCCCUGCUGCGCUCGGGGGCACGGGCCUGCCUGGGGAAGCAGCUGGGGGGCUCUGCCUGGGCCCUGGCCACAUGCAGCCCUGCGUGUGUCCCCUCGACGCCACGUGUAGUGAGGUGAGCGCCCCAGUGCCCACCUGUGAGCCUGGCAGUGGACUGGGUGGGUGCCGGCUCCCUGAUGAGGAUGGUGCAGAGAGACUAUGGGUGUGGGGCGGGGGCGGGGGGCACCUCCAGGCCUCGCACAGGGCCCCUUGGCUGUCCCAGUAGGACCUGACUGGCCAGCCUAUGUGGAGGGCGUCCAGCUUGUCUCCCCCAACCCUGGCCGGAUGCUGUCUCCAUGCCAGCUGGCCCAGGGGUGGCCAGAUGUCACUUAGCCCUGAACGAAUUCUGCAUGAAUUCUGCCAUCCAGGCAGAGGCUGCGUGUGGGGAGGAGCUCACGGCACCUUCCAGCCUCUGGCCCCAGGUUGGCCCCCUCCCCAGCUGAGUCCCCCUCCUGGGUGGGUGCCAUAGGCCUGGGAGACCCUGUGGCCGGGCUCAGGGAGGCUUCUGAGGCCUGUGAGUUCACCUCACUGUGUGUGGGUCCUGUCUGUGCUUGGCUGAGGGUCAGGGAAGUGGUAAUCUGGGCUCCACAGAAUCGGGGGCAUCAUCUGGUUGGGGAUUUCGGGGGCACACGUACCACAUAGAGGACUGGGCCAGGAGCCAUGGCAGGGGUCUGUGUGUGGGUGAGUAUGGGAGGAUGUGAUUGUGAGUGCCUUUGUGCAUGGGAGGGUGUGAUUGUGUAUAUGAGUGCAUGAGAGGAUGUGACUGAGUGUGCAUGUGUGGGUGUGACAGUGCAGGUGUGACUGCAUGUGAAGGUGUCACUGAGUGUGCACGAGAGGGUGUGACUGCAUGUGAGAGUGUGUGACUGCAUGGGAGGAUAUGAGUGUGCAUGAGUGUGCAUGUGAGGGUGUGACUGAGUGCAUGAGAGUGUGACUGCCUGUGAGUGAAUGUGUGACUGCAUGUGCGAGUGACUGCCUGGGAGGAUGUGAUUGUGCAUGAGUGUGCAUGUGGGUGUGACUGCAUGUGAGGGUGUGACUGUUGUGCGUGUGAAGGCUUGAUUGUGAGUGUGCCUGGGAGGAUGUGAGUGUGAGGGUGUGACUCCCUGUGACAUGAGUGUGCAUGCAUGUGAGUGUGAGGAAGAGUGUGUAGGUGUGAGUGUCUAGGCAGGUGUGUCUGCAGUGUGUGCAGCAUGUGCGUAAGUGCAUGUGAAUGUGCGUGUGUUGCAUGUGAGCAUGUGCACGCCUGUGCGUGUGAGCAUUGUGUGCGUGAUGGGAGCCGUGGGUGCUGUGUGGACAGCCCCUCUGCCCCUCCCAUGGGCUCCCACGCCCAGCAUCCACCUGAGAGAGGAGGGAGCUGCCUUCCCAUUCUGCAGAGUCUGUGUGCUGAGGCCCCGCAGAAGCAAGUGGAGGAGCUGGGAUGUGAACCUGGGACCCCGGCGUAGGGGGCUGCUUGGCUGUGGACCCUGCCCCUCAGGAAAGCCCAGGGUCCACCUCCAGAGGACUCGUUCUGGGGCGGGGGCGGAGGCGGGGGGCCUCCCCACCCGGGGCUCGAUGAGGGGCUGUCCGUUUCUUGGCUCGAGUGCUGCCAAGUGCUCCCUGCUGCUGCGCCCACCUUCCCGGGGAGAGGCGAGCCCCUGGCUCCCUGAGUUCAUGACCCACCCUGUCCACCAUCAGCAGCUGGCUUGUGUCUCUGGGUGGCUGGGCACCAGCCUCCUGGAGGCCACGUGCCUGGGUCCACAUGGAGGGUCCUGGUGGGGGCAUCAUCCUGGGUCCCGGGAGUGAGGCUGGCAGGUGCCCAUCGGGGGUGUCAAGUCCAGGGGGAUCGAGGCUCUGGAAGCUCAAGGGGGCUCUGGCCUUGGGGACCAGCUGAGUUUCCAGCUGGCAGCCAGGUCCUCGAGGGAAGGGGUUUGGACAGAAUCCGAGGCCCCCUAAGCUGAUGGGGUCCCCUGUCUCCCCUUCCAGCCCUGACCCACUGGACAUGGGGACUCUUUCCAGUCCGGAGAGCUCCUUGUCUGUGUCCCCAGCAGAAGGUGGGGUGGCUCCUGCCUCACCCUCUGCCCAGCCCUGAUCCAGGCCACAGCCAUCUAGGGCCCUGAAGGAGGGGCAGGAGGCAGGGGUGGCUUCUGGAACCUGAGGCUUGGCCCCGGUUGGGUCUGUUCUUGGGGGCUGCACUGCUGGAUCCCAGGAGCAGGUGUGGAACAGCCCCAUGGCCAGGGUGAUGGAAAUCCUCGGCUGCAUGCAGACAUAGACCCACCCUGGACUGGGCUGUCUCCGGAGCCCAGACACAUCGCCCUGGGAAGGGGCAGCUGGGCCUGCAGUGUGCUGGGCAGGGGCUGGCGGCCCUGGUCGUGGGCUCUCCAGGGUCCCUCAGGGGAUUGGGCCUCUCCCCAGGCAGGAAGGUGGGAAGUGCAGGCAUGACCCGGGGUUCCUGAGGCUGGUCCACCAAGUUGCUUCUGAGACGCCUUCGCUUCUGUCCUGGCUGGCUGUUAAUGAUAUCCCUGUUCUAAUUCCACUCUGGCUAAACUGAAAGUAAAGAUCCUUAAGCUUA